AGUGACGCGCUCGUGGGGAAAAGGCAGGGAGGGGGUGGUGUCCCCAGCCGGUUUGGGGGGUGCGUUGCCCGGAGACGGAAAGUUUGGGAGCCCGAGCAGGCUCGGCUGCAGCCUCGGGGAGGGGGUCCAGCGGGUGGCGGCCCUGGGGAUGGGGAAGGAGCAGGAGCUGCUGGAGGCGGCCCGCACCGGGCACCUCCCGGCGGUGGAGAAGCUGCUGUCCGGGAAGCGGCUCUCCUCAGGCUUUGGGGGCGGCGGCGGCGGUGGCUCUGGGGGCGGCGGCGGCGGCAGCGGCGGCGGCGGCGGCGGCCUCGGCUCUUCCAGCCACCCCCUCUCCAGUCUGCUCAGCAUGUGGAGAGGGCCAAAUGUGAACUGUGUUGACAGCACUGGCUACACACCCCUGCACCAUGCUGCUUUGAAUGGCCAUAAGGAUGUGGUCGAGGUUCUUCUGAGGAACGAUGCGCUGACCAACGUGGCUGACUCAAAAGGCUGCUACCCUCUGCAUUUGGCAGCCUGGAAAGGAGAUGCCCAGAUAGUGCGGUUGCUCAUCCAUCAAGGGCCUUCACACACCAGAGUCAAUGAACAGAAUGCUCUUGAGAUCAAAGAACUCAAAAAGUACGGCCCCUUUGACCCUUAUAUCAAUGCCAAGAACAAUGACAACGAGACAGCCCUGCAUUGUGCAGCGCAGUAUGGCCACACAGAGGUGGUGAAGGUGCUCUUAGAGGAGCUGACGGACCCCACCAUGCGCAACAACAAAUUCGAGACCCCUUUGGACCUGGCAGCACUGUACGGGCGACUGGAGGUGGUGAAAAUGCUCCUUAAUGCACACCCCAACCUCCUGAGCUGCAACACUAAGAAGCACACCCCUCUGCACUUGGCAGCAAGGAAUGGCCACAAAGCCGUGGUCCAGGUCCUCCUCGAUGCUGGCAUGGACAGCAACUACCAGACGGAGAUGGGCAGUGCUUUGCAUGAGGCUGCUUUGUUUGGCAAGACCGAUGUGGUGCAAAUCCUGCUGGCUGCAGGAACUGACGUCAACAUAAAAGAUAACCAUGGACUGACUGCCCUAGACACUGUUCGGGAACUGCCUUCUCAAAAGAGCCAGCAAAUAGCAGCAUUAAUUGAAGAUCACAUGACUGGAAAAAGAAGUACAAAAGAAGUAGAUAAAACCCCCCCACCCCAGCCACCUCUCAUCUCCAGUAUGGACUCCAUAUCACAGAAGUCUCAGGGUGACGUGGAGAAAGCAGUGACUGAACUGAUUAUAGAUUUUGAUGCAAAUGCUGAAGAAGAGGGUCCCUACGAAGCUCUGUAUAAUGCCAUCUCCUGCCAUUCGUUGGACAGCAUGGCCAGCGGGCGAUCAUCUGACCAAGACUCCACGAACAAGGAGGCUGAGGCAGCAGGAGUGAAACCUGCUGGAGUGAGGCCUAGGGAACGUCCACCACCUCCAGCAAAGCCACCGCCCGAUGAAGAGGAAGAAGACCACAUAGAUAAGAAGUAUUUUCCCUUGACAGCUUCUGAGGUUCUGUCCAUGAGACCUAGGAUUCAUGGGAGUGCAGCCCGGGAAGAAGACGAACACCCUUAUGAACUGUUGUUAACAGCAGAGACAAAGAAAGUGGUGUUGGUGGAUGGAAAAACAAAAGACCACAGGCGGAGCAGCAGCAGCCGGAGCCAGGACUCUGCGGAGGGGCAGGACGGGCAGGUCCCAGAGCAGUUCUCAGGCCUCCUCCACGGCUCCUCCCCGGUGUGCGAGGUGGGGCAGGACCCUUUCCAGCUGCUCUGUACCGCUGGCCAGAGCCAUCCAGACGGGUCCCCCCAGCAGGGCGCCUGCCACAAGGCCAGCAUGCAGCUGGAGGAGACGGGUGUGCAUGCUCCUGGAGCCUCCCAGCCCAGUGCCCUGGACCAGAGCAAGAGAGUGGGCUACCUCACAGGCCUGCCCACCACCAACAGCCGCUCGCACCCUGAAACUUUGACUCACACAGCAUCUCCGCACCCUGGUGGUGCUGAGGAAGGAGACCGGAGUGGGGCCAGGAGCCGAGCGCCUCCCACUAGCAAACCCAAAGCUGAACUCAAACUCAGCCGCAGCUUGUCCAAGUCUGACUCUGAUCUCCUGACCUGCUCACCCACAGAGGACGCUACCAUGGGGAGUCGGAGUGAGUCCUUAUCCAACUGCAGCAUUGGGAAGAAAAGGCUAGAGAAGUCACCCUCCUUCGCCUCGGAGUGGGAUGAGAUUGAGAAAAUCAUGAGUUCUAUUGGAGAAGGGAUUGACUUUUCUCAGGAACGGCAGAAGAUCUCAGGUUUACGGACGCUGGAGCAGAGUGUCGGGGAGUGGCUGGAGUCGAUUGGGCUGCAGCAGUAUGAGAGCAAGUUGCUUCUGAAUGGCUUUGACGAUGUCCACUUCCUGGGGUCUAAUGUGAUGGAAGAGCAGGACCUGCGGGACAUCGGCAUCAGCGACCCACAGCACCGGCGGAAGCUGCUCCAGGCGGCACGCUCCCUACCCAAGGUGAAGGCUCUGGGUUAUGACGGGAACAGCCCCCCUAGCGUGCCCUCCUGGCUGGACUCCCUGGGGCUGCAGGACUACGUCCAUUCCUUCUUGUCAAGUGGUUACAGCUCCAUUGACACCGUGAAGAACCUCUGGGAGCUAGAGCUCGUCAAUGUCCUGAAGGUCCAGCUGCUCGGCCAUCGCAAGCGCAUCAUCGCCUCCCUCGCAGACAGACCGUACGAGGAGCCGCCCCAGAAGCCCCCCAGAUUCUCCCAGCUGAGGUGCCAAGAUUUGCUCUCCCAGACGUCAUCCCCACUGAGUCAGAAUGAUUCCUGCACUGGGCGGUCGGCAGAUCUGCUGCUGCCUCCAGGGGACACAGGCAGGAGGCGCCAUGACAGUCUCCAUGACCCUGCGGCACCCUCCCGAGCGGAGCGCUUCAGGAUCCAGGAGGAGCACCGUGAGGCCAAGCUGACCCUGCGGCCCCCGAGCCUGGCAGCCCCCUACGCCCCAGUGCAGAGUUGGCAACACCAGCCAGAGAAACUCAUCUUCGAGUCCUGUGGUUAUGAAGCCAAUUAUCUGGGCUCCAUGCUGAUCAAAGAUCUGCGAGGGACAGAAUCCACGCAAGACGCCUGUGCCAAGAUGCGGAAAUCUACGGAGCACAUGAAGAAGAUCCCCACCAUCAUCCUGUCCAUCACAUACAAAGGUGUCAAGUUCAUCGAUGCCUCCAACAAGCAGAACGUCAUUGCAGAGCACGAGAUCCGGAACAUUUCCUGUGCGGCCCAGGACCCGGAGGACCUCUGUACCUUUGCCUACAUCACCAAGGACCUGCAGACCAGCCACCACUAUUGCCAUGUGUUCAGCACCGUGGAUGUGAACCUGACCUACGAGAUCAUCCUGACGCUGGGGCAGGCCUUCGAAGUGGCCUAUCAGUUGGCCCUGCAGGCCCAGAAGUCCAGGGCGACGGGCGCCUCUGCAGCUGAGAUGAUUGAAACAAAAUCUUCCAAACCGGUGCCUAAGCCUCGGGUCGGCGUGAGGAAAUCCGCACUGGAACCACCUGAUAUGGACCAAGAUGCCCAAUCCCAUGCCAGUGUCUCCUGGGUUGUGGACCCCAAACCAGACUCUAAGCGGAGCCUCAGCACCAACUGAGCCACUGAGGAACCACACUGUGCUGCGGAAACAUAGACGUGGGGGCAUAGGCUCCCACUGCCACCACCGCCAUCGCCUCACCUGCAGCUCUGAAGACCCAGGCCUCACCUCCGCCUGCAGGACCUCCUCUUGGCCACUUGGCCUGGGCCUGCCACCACCACGUCCUGCAGAACGAGCCCUGCCUUGGCUGUGGAGAAGCACUCCAGGCCGCUAGCAGAUGGGACUGGCAUUCCAGAGGGUCAAGAAGUGACUUGUUCAGAACACAUUGUUUUUAACAGAAAAAAAAUCUUUUUAUAAAAUGAACUUUUAACACUUGGCUCAAACCUCUAGGUCAUACUGCCAAUCUUUAGACAAAUGGCCAUGGGGCAGAGGACAGGGGAGCUGAGGUUGGUUCAGAGGCCAGCCUGCAUAGCCUCUGUCCUCAGGACGGAACUUGGGUGCAGCUCAGUGGGUCGGAAGAGAAGGCGGUGGCCUGUGGGUGAGGGGAACGGAGCAGGCUCAGGCAGAAUUGAGUACGGUGCGUCUGCUUUUCAAACCCAACCAUAUCAGCUGCUGCUCUUUAUGAACUGCCCAACUUCCUGUCCCUUUCAGGGGCUAGACACAGGCUUCUCGUAAGAACACAGCCUUAGAGGCACCUGAGCAACUCAAAGGUUUCCGGUCCAUUUCUGGGGUUCCCGAUGGGAAGGUUCAGUGGCCAAAUGAAGAUAAGUGUGCAGUUUCUAGUGCUGGGAAGUCUUAGCCAGCACCAGAGCGCCAGGCCUCUCCCUGGCCUCUUACCUGUCAGUGAUCGGAGCACUGCCCUGGGCUGGCCGGCGCCGUACUGCCUGCGUUGUGUCAGAGAAUAGGAAAAGCAGCUUUGUUUGGGGCAUUAAUGCUUGGAGUGGGGUCAGCUAAGGUUGCUACUUGCCAAUUUGUGAUUUGUCUAAUCAGCCUGUGUGAUUGGGGCUCAUUUUGAUUCUCUGAAUUAUCGGUUUGACGGUUACACUUGGCUGCUGGGCCCAUCCCUGGCCCCCGGUGUGGAAAAGGCUAAAUAAGGUGACAGUGCAUCGAUGCUCCCCCGCGUGGCCUUUGGGGCAGGCUGGCAUCCCGGUGCGCCUCUGCUUCUUAAGCUUUCCUGCUGCUCGCUUUGUUUUUAAAAGUAACUUGGGUUGCAUUCUUCCCUCUGGACUAGAGUAGAAAUGCAGGGGAAACUGCUGUGGAUUUGAGAGGCAAAGUUGGCUCAGCUGUGUGCCCAGUUCCUCCUGUGGGCACUUUAGCAGGCUCCGAGCUUUCCUGGCAUAGGUCAAUCAGGUCCCAGGAUGAAUAAUCCAGGCUUCAGCAACACUCCUCUUUCCCAGCCAGCAAAGGCUGUGAAUUUGAAUUCUUUGUUGGUAUGUAUGUGCAGGGAGUACUGUUAGGCACAUUCUUAACCCAUGUGGUUGGCCAGAAAUCAGAAGUGGGGCUGUGUCUCUGACUGGCUAGAGGCCAGGCCUUGUGGGUUUCUAUCUGCUAAGCACCCAGCAGGUUGGGGCCUGGGACUCAGCUCUCUCUGCGGUAGAGGCAGGCCCUCCUCCACUUCUUGGUACUAAACGAAGAUCUCGACACCUUGCAGUUUUACUUCAUUUCCUGCCCCUUUCAGGGCCUGUGAGGAUGCCCAUGAGCUACCGCUGUACAGUUCUCGGCCCCGGCUUUCUUCCAAGAGUUGACCAGGAACCCUAAAGCAUCCAGAGUAGACUGCGCUGCCACUGCGCACAUGCUGGUGCCCGUCUUCCUCCUAAGGGGCCAGGCCACAUCCAAGUGGGCCUCUGUCGGGGGCGGGGCGGUAGGUCCGAAAGAAACCGCAGACACUACGAUGCACUCCUCAAGCUGUCUUUUGUGCUUAGAUCAUCCAUAGGUGUUUCUUCUGCUUGAAGCUGCUAUAUCAUCUUUAUUUAUUCAGGGUAUUUUCAUAUUGGAAGCCUUGGCUAGUCUGCUCUAGCUCUGGGUUCUGUUUAGAGAUUGGUUUAUUUCUGAAUAUUCAAGAAAGGAAAAUGACUGGGCCUUUCUUUCUUUUCUUCUCCUCUGGGAUGGGUAGUCUCCCUUUCCUAGAAAGGUUAUUAUAACUUUAAGGACAGGCUUCAAGUGGGAAGGCCCCUACUUUUGCACUUCUCCAAGUGCAGGUCACACCAGGGGCAGACCCUGUCGCUGCGUUUCUGAACUGUGAAGGAGCCCAUUCGGGUGGGAGACUUCAGAUGGGCUCAGUACCUGUCCCAGCCACAGGCUUCUUGUCCACCUCUUCUCCCCUGCCCACCAGCUGCUCAGCGCAUAAGACCUUCCCGACAGGCUCUGCGUGUGCAGCUCUCUGCGUCCCUCCUGGGCCCUCCAGCGUCAGACACUAAUGGGAGUUCCCGAGAUGCUCGGGUUUGAGCAGGGAGCAGGCAGAGCUGCAGUCAGAGACAUUAGAAAACCAGUCUGAAUUGGGUCUGUCUUUGAGAUGCCCAGGCCAGCAGAAAGCAGCUCAGAAGUAUUGUUGCUCAUGGUGUGGCAAUGGACUGAACUGUAAUGAAAAUGUUAUUUAAUCUUUGUCUCUGUAUUUUGAUACUUGAAUGACUUUCCCUUUUGUUUUACUGUAUAUAAAAUUGUUAAUCUGUCUGAUUUUGUCUGAAUUAUAAACACUUUGAGGUACCAAACAUAACCAAUCUGUGCAACAACAUAGACUGACCUCAGUACCCAAGAGAGUGUAAAUAUUUCUGGGCUUCCAGCUUUGGUUUUGUUAUUUUCAUAACUGUACACAACUUAGAACAGACUGAAUUAAUAAAUGAGAAGCGACAUGAACGCA